GGAUUACAGGCGUGAGCCACCACGCCCGGCCCCUUAUGCUCUUUUUGUAUUUCAAGGGAAUGCUAUCGGUUAACUAAGGGACAAAACUUUACCACAGAGAGGCAAGCUCGCUUUUCCCAAGCCACACAGCACAGAGGACUAAGAAGGAGAUUUUCAAAGCUCUGACUGUGCAGUCAGGUCUCAUUGGGCAGCAUUCACAGAGGAAGAGAAGCAGCCAGAUGGGACAGGUACUGUAGAGACAGGCAGGGUGGGCAAGAAUGUUGCUCUGGAGUCAGAAGCAGCUGAGUUACAAACCUGGGGACCUUCACAUAGUGCACUCCUCAAGAGCAAGGCCAAUGUCUUAAUGAUGUCUCUGCGUUUAUUUGGACCUUAAACAUGGACCUCAGGUGCUGAAUAAAUGACUCUUGACUUGUAGCGGUUGACUUGCAUGACUGUCGUGUGGCCUGAAACCUCAGUUUCCUCAUCUGUAAUAGGAUAAAAAUGACUGCUAGCCUGGGAGCCCUCCUGAGUAGUUUGCUAUCUGGGACGAUUUUCAUGCAUCCUUCUUGGGAGAGAUUUUUCCCUCCACAAAUCUCAAGCUGCCUUCAGUCCUGUUGCCACAUUGCUUAACUGAGAAAGUACAGGGAACAGAGAAGUAGAUAUCUCAGACCUGAUUGGCUCCAUUUGGUGACUAGAUACAGACAGUGUCCUUCCCACCACCACGGCCAAUGACUCUCCUGUCAAGAGGGCGCUCUGUGGAGAAGCAGAAAUGCUGUGUCCGUGAGGGCUGUCUGGAUGGCAUGAGGUUUCAAAUACCAUAUUGCAGUCAGGAGUUUUGGGUACUGAAUCAUGUAUUUACUCAUAUAUAUAUAUGAGUAUAUUAAAAAAGAAAAAGAUAGAGAUAUAUAUGUAUGUGUGUGUGUGUGUGUGUGUGUGUGUGUGUGUGUGUGUAUAUAUAUAUAUUUGAGACUGAGCCUCACUCUAUCGCCCACGCUGGAGUGCAGUGGCACAAUCUCGGCUUGCUGCAACUUCUGCCUCCCUGGUUCAAGUGAUUCUCAUGCCUCAGCCUCCCAAGUAGCUGGGAUUAUAGGCAGCCACCACCAGGCCCAGCUAAUUUUUGUAUUUUUGGUAGAGACAGGGUUUCACCAUGUUGACCAGGCUGGUCUCAAACUCCUGAUCUCAGUGAUCCACCUACCUUGGCCUCCCAAAGUGCUGGGAUUACAGGUGUGAGCCACCGUGCCCAGCCUAUUUACUCAUAUAUUUACAAAACAAAAUUAAACAUCUGACCCUCUCAAGAUUGACAACUACUCAGUACACUGAUUUAUGGACUUUUAAUCACAACGUCUAAAACCAACCCCUGUUACGGGACAACCAGAGAUGACUUGACUGCUGGCCGUUCAGGGCAGAGCCACCAGGUGCAUGGAGGUUUCUAACAAUACCAGCUUCAUAAGUUUGUCAUGAGGUAGCUUAGUCCAUUUUUAUUACUAUAAAGGAAUACCUGAGGCUGGGUAAUCUAUAAAGAAAAGAGGAUUAUUUGGCUCUCAGUUCUGCAGACUAUAUGGGAGGCAUGACUCCAGCAUCUGCUUCUGUCAAGAACCUCAGGAAGCUUCCACUCAUGACAGAAGGCAAAGGAAGGAGACAUAUGGAGAGAAGAAGGGAGAGAGAGAGGGGAGAAGCUGCCAGGCUCUUUUCAACAACCAGCUCCCGUGAAAACAAAGAGUGAGAACUUACUCCCAGAAGACUGGCUCCAAGCCAUUCAUGAGCAAUCCACUUCCAUGAUCCAAACGCCUCCCACCAGGCCCCACCUCCAACAUUGGGGAUCAAAUUUCAACAUGAGACUUGGUGGGGUCAAGCAAUGCCAUGCCAUAAAGGUUUAAAGUCUGAAGUGCCUGGUACAUAAAGACCCUCAAUUAUGAUAGACUCCCUUAUCCUCAUUUUUCUUCUACUAGAGAAACAAAUAGAUGGAGAGUCACCUGUGUGCCCUCUGUUCUCAAGAUGGCCGCCAGCCCCAGGCACUCUGUUGAGCAGCCUCAGAGCAUCCUGUGAGGAUGUUCAUGACUGAUUCAGCAGUUCACAGAGCACAACAAAAGGCUGUGGUAUUUCUACCUAAAACUACUUUAUGAAAAAGUGUUGUUUUCCAAAUAUACCCCAAAAGAAUACCUCCAUCUUCCGUUGUGGCAACAAUGACCACUGUGUGGCUGGACUCUUCAACCAGGGAAAAGAGGAGUUGGGUUCUACCUCAGUUUACCCAUCCCCCAGUUCAUUGCCGACUUUUAAACUGAUUUUGAGGGAGAAGAAUGAGGCAUCUGAUUAAUUAGGUCAUCUUUUAAUUGAAUUCAAACUGUUAGGUGUGGAAAAUUUAACAAGUGGUAUCCAGGAGGUUGAGAACAUUUUUUAAAAUAUUGUAGUUCGUAUUAAAUGUUUCCAAAUGUAAGAUCAUCUUAGCUACAUGAAGGAAAGAUAUAAUUUAAUAUUGGUUGCAUAGGGAAUUUCAUCCACUUGAAGGAUUACAUGCUUGACCCUGUGCCUUCCCAUUUCCUAAGUGAACAAGUCCUUGGUCACAGAGAACCAAUGCAUGGAGCAGGUACAGUGCCUACCGCCACGCAUGUGAGUCCACCAGCAAUGCAAAGUCAAGGACAAUACAGCUCCAAGUAACUGGAAAGCUCAACCAAUUAGUUUUCUACUUAAUUGAAUCAAAGUCUUACUAUUUUGAGGGAAUAUGUUUUUCAUUCCGUUAUCCUACAUCUUGUCUCUUGCUUUUUACUGCAGGUGUCAGAUAUUUGAGUUUUAUCAAAUGGCACUAAAAUAGGGGAACUCUCUUCUGAAGGCAUAUGCUGAGCACCCCUAGAGAACCUGCUGGUCUGGGAUAACCUAUCCCUCUGAGUCGGGGAUGUCUUAAGUGUUUUUUUUUUUUUUGACCAUAGCAUUGAGUGAUUUGGGAGCAGAAGGUAUUCCUUAGACAGGAAAUAGGAGCUCAAUAGAUGGCCCAAAAGAAGUGUCUGGAUUACAAACGCAAAGAGACAAGAAAGUGCAGUCAAGCCAACAAAGAAAACGGCAGCUAACAAGACUGGUUGUGUCUCUUUAAUGAUACCUGGUCCCACUAUUCGCCUGGAACAAUACUAAGCUCACUGUCACUGUCACCCCCAGCCCCAACUUGUUUCUACUCCUGCAUUUUCAUUCAGAGAGUGUCUCCACCACCCACUAAAUAUUCAAGCUGCAGUGCCAGAUCAGUCUCAGCUUUAUUCAGUCAACCAUCGAAACAUCAUUGCCAAUAUCCUCAUUGUCACUGCCUCAGUUCAACCUCUCAAUGUGUUCUUCCCACCUAUUGUCAAGGCCUUCUAGCCUCCCAGCAUCCAGCUUAUCUCUCUGAAAUGUAUCCUUCAAUGCAAGCAAAUCUGAACAUGCCUCUCUAGCUUAAUUUGAGAUCAGGUCCAAGCUCUAAAGUGACGCAUAAGGCCUUUGCGAGUGAUCUCCCACUUACGUUUUCAGGUAUCUGCAAAGGCCUUUAUCUUUACCCUCAUCCAGCUUUACAGUUUUGGCCCUAGCAUUACCAAGCUUGGAUUUUCCUGCACAUGCAGUGCUGUCUCUUGCUUUCAUCUGUUUGCUGGUGCCAUUCUCUCUACUUCAGAUGUCCUUCUGCUUUCCUUUCUUUCUCUAGUCAGCUCUUACUUUGCUUUUUUUUUUUUUUUCUGAGAUGGAGUUUUGCUCUUGUCACCCAGGGUGGAGUGCAAUGGCACGACCUCGGCUCACUGCAUCCUCCGCCUCCCAGGUUCAAGUGAUUCUCCUGCCUCAGCCUCCCAAGUAGCUGGGAUUACAGGCACCCACCACCACGCCACCACGCCCGGCUAAUUUUUGUAUUUUUAGUAGACACGGGGUUUCACCAUGUUGGUCAGGCUGGUCUCGAACUCCUCUCCUCAGGUGAUCCACCCGCCUUGGCCUCCCAAAGUGCUGGGAUUACAGGCGUGAGCCACCGUGUCCAGCCUCUUACUUAGCUUUUAAGGUCCAGAUCAAGCAUCAUUUCUUUUAGGAAAGAGUCCUAAACUUUCUCAGCCCACAACCCCUUAGUGUCCAAUAAUUUUUACAUAGAGCCUGUGGGCCAACAAAAAUACCAACAGUUCUGUUUAUUUAGUAGUUAGAUCUAAACACCUUAAUAAGUAUUUAUGUCCUGGCAACUUAAGAGCUGUGUUAAAACACACACACACACACACACACACACACACACACACACACACUAAAAUAAUAAUCACCUUUUUAUUCUUAAAUAACCACAGCUACUUACUAAUGGGAUGUGUGUGUCUGUGGGGCACUGCACAACUGCCCCAGCCUUAGGAUCAGUUGGGGCACUGCCACUCUCAUUGCCUGUUCCACAUUGAUUUUCGCUGGAUACUUGGUUUUUAUUACAACAGUUGCUAAAACUGCAGCUUCACCAAGAUAGGACCUCAAGAAUGCAGCCCAGUCUGAUAUUGUGAACUCUAACUACCUCAAGCUAGAAGCUUAUGUGGUGUUCAACAGAUGAUGAGUAUUGCUGUGUUUCUCUUAUAACAUUUAAAAUAUCCAGUGGCACCUCUUUGAGUCUGCUGUGGCGUUCUGACCUAGAGUAGCUUGGUGUACAAUUUGAGAGCCUCAGGCUUGGGAACUCCCCACUACGGAGGUGGGCCCACCGUGAGCUCUCUUGACACCCUGCACGUCUCCGUCAUGGCCCUUGGCAUAUUGCAUUGUAAGAAGCUGCUUUUGUAUCUGACUCUCUGAGGCUGUGAGCUCUCUAAGGGUAGGGACCAUACCUUCCUCCUCUUUGUACAUCCCGUGAUAAUUCAGGGGUUUUGUUUUUGGUUUUCAUUUGGUUUCCUGAUAAGCGUUCCUUAGGAGAAGAAGAAAAAAGAGAGUAGAAGGAAAAGAAAGAAGGGAGAGGAGGGAGGGAAAGAAGGAAGGAAGAAAGAGAGAGAGGGAAGGAGGAAGAGGAGGGAGGGAAAGCAGAAAGAAGGAAAGCUGCUUUGUCUCAGGCAGACUAACAGGAAAGCGACUUUUCCUUGCAAACCUCCUUCAAGGUCAUGAGAGAUAUCUCUGUGACCCUGGGGCCAGACCAACCUUGAAUUCAAAAAUCCUCCAAGCUGAGGGCAGAAAGUAGGAAGAAUCCCGCCGGAGCACUGCAAGGCCAUUGGCGGGCACUGCUGUUCCCUCCCCUGUGGGAAGGACCACUGCUCACCUGGGUUUUUUUAAUUAGCCAUUGUGUUUCUUUUCUUUGUGCUGUUCUUCUCCAUCCUUAGUAGGCAGGAGAGUUUUUACACUAUUUCUUUUUCAUAUUCUGCUAUAAAUGAGCCCUACACAUAAUCAGGAAGGUUAGGGCUAGGAUCAGAAGUCAAAUUUAGGUUCACACAUGACAAAACUUCAACAAUUCACAUUUCACCAGUUCUAAACAAGAAGGUUCCAUUUAAAUCACUGAUUGCUGUAAUUUGUUGCUAUCAUCCAAUGGGUGCAUUUUAGUUUAAAGGGAUAUGCCUCCUUUAUCUUCUCGAGGUCUCAGACAGUGUCUGAGUAAACUCUCUGCCAAGUCCUGAGUCACCCGGAGGAUAGCAGAUGCGCAGACUCAGUCUGGGGUUUAGGGUCCACUCCGCAUACUCCCACUUGCCCUUGGCAUUGGCCCCAUGGGUGGACCAUGGAGGUGGGUGCUGUAUGGCAACAGUCAUUCCUCAGCAGAGUGGAGAGGGAGACACAUGUUCUGCCGCGCCCAUGUUCAGUCUGUUCUGUGGGCAGAGUUGUAGGAACACACUUAGCCCAAAUCGAUGCCAGCCUGGCAGUGGGUGAAGGGCCAGCAAGGUUUGUCUAUGGCUCAUGACCUUAGGGAAAAUGAGAUUUUACUCCUCGUGCAGCCUCCUGCCUGGAGAAUUGCACACCCCUGUUUCAGAUAGGUAACAGCUUUCUUGAAGCUUUCAAGAAUAAAAAUAAAAACUUUAAAGUACAUGGCUGUCAGAAAGUCCCUCCUGGUAGCUAACUUGAGCCCUUUGUGCUUAUUUUAUCUUGGCCAAGCCUCCCCGGAGCAUGUGUACCAGAUACGAUAACCUUCCACCAAACCAGGGACCUCUCAGAUCUCGGCUUUUCAGAACAAAGAAUUUGGAUUUCCUUAGCCUUUCAUCAUCAUCUCAUCACCCAAACCUUUCAUUAUCUUUUUCAAUUUUUUCUUUGAACUCUUUCCAAAACUUGUCUUUUGAGUUACAGAGACCAUCACUUAAUUAGAUCUUUCAUUUCCAGGGGAUACUCCUAGUGCCUAGGAAGAAAUAAAUUAAAUUUCACUCGGAUAUAUUUCAUUGGGGGAAGGGUGUAGAAAAAAAGAAAUUGAAUUCCUUAUAUAAAUAGCACAUUGUCUGGUGCCACAAAUGCGUUUUCCUUUUCCCAGUUGUUUUUGGAACAAUGGGUCCUUUUUUGGUGACUUUAAUUCCUCAGAGAUUCUAACCUCUAAAAGGUCAUGAUUUGUGUUGUUUUGUGCAUACACGGCUUCUGUACUGAAAAAAAAAAAGCGAGAUGUGUGGCCUCUGAUUGUCUAGUAAGUCGUGAGGAAACAGACAAGGCUGCAACCCAGCAGCAGUUGAGCACCUUGUCAAAGUGUGGGAAUGAGCGUGUGUGGGUCUCUGUGCUUCCAGCCUUUUCUGCACCAGCUGUUCCAAGCGGAGCAGAGGGGUCUGUCUUGCUUCUCCGUAACUUCAUCAACCUACAAAAAGCCUUGGCAUCCACGGGAGGAAGAAGUGUUCAGGCAGCAUGUGACUGGUUAUUCUCCCAUGUCGGUGACCCCUUCCUGGAUGACCCCCUGCCCCGGGAGUACGUCCUCUACCUCCGUCCCACCGGCCCCUUAGCACAGAAGCUUUCCGACUUUUGGCAGCAGUCGAAGCAGAUCUGCGGGAAGAACAAGGCACACAACAUCUUCCCCCACAUCACACUCUGCCAGUUCUUUAUGUGCGAGGACAGCAAGGUGGAUGCCCUGGGGGAAGCCCUGCAGACCACGGUCAGUCGCUGGAAAUGUAAGUUCUCGGCCCCGCUGCCCCUGGAGCUCUAUACGUCGUCCAACUUCAUCGGCCUCUUUGUAAAGGAAGACAGUGCGGAGGUCCUCAAGAAGUUUGCUGCUGACUUUGCUGCAGAGGCUGCAUCCAAAACCGAAGUGCAUGUGGAACCUCAUAAGAAGCAGCUACAUGUGACCCUGGCUUACCACUUCCAAGCCAGCCACCUACCCACCCUAGAGAAACUGGCCCAGAACAUUGACGUCAAGCUAGGGUGUGACUGGGUGGCUACCAUAUUUUCUCGGGAUAUCCGAUUUGCUAACCAUGAGACAUUACAGGUCAUCUACCCCUAUACCCCACAAAAUGACGAUGAGCUGGAGCUGGUCCCCGGGGACUUCAUCUUCAUGUCUCCAAUGGAGCAGACCAGCACCAGCGAGGGUUGGAUCUAUGGCACGUCCUUAACCACCGGCUGCUCUGGACUCCUGCCUGAGAAUUACAUUACCAAGGCUGAUGAAUGCAGCACCUGGAUAUUUCAUGGUUCUUAUUCAAUCUUAAAUACAUCGUCAUCCAACUCUCUCACGUUUGGGGAUGGAGUAUUGGAGAGGCGGCCUUAUGAGGACCAGGGGCUCGGGGAGACGACUCCUCUUACUAUCAUCUGCCAGCCCAUGCAGCCGCUGAGGGUCAACAGCCAGCCCGGCCCCCAGAAGCGAUGCCUUUUUGUGUGUCGGCAUGGUGAGAGGAUGGAUGUUGUGUUUGGGAAGUACUGGCUGUCCCAGUGCUUCGAUGCCAAAGGCCGCUACAUACGCACCAACCUGAACAUGCCUCAUAGUUUACCUCAGCGGAGUGGUGGUUUCCGAGAUUACGAGAAAGAUGCUCCCAUCACUGUGUUUGGAUGCAUGCAAGCAAGACUAGUGGGUGAAGCCUUAUUAGAGAGCAAUACCAUUAUCGAUCAUGUCUAUUGCUCCCCGUCCCUUCGCUGCGUUCAGACUGCACACAAUAUCUUGAAAGGUUUACAACAAGAAAAUCACUUGAAGAUCCGUGUAGAGCCCGGCUUAUUUGAGUGGACAAAAUGGGUUGCUGGGAGCACAUUACCUGCAUGGAUACCUCCAUCAGAGUUAGCUGCAGCCAACCUGAGUGUUGAUACAACCUACAGACCUCACAUUCCAAUCAGCAAAUUAGUUGUUUCAGAAUCCUAUGAUACUUAUAUCAGUAGAAGUUUCCAAGUAACAAAAGAAAUAAUAAGUGAAUGUAAAAGUAAAGGAAAUAACAUCCUGAUUGUGGCCCACGCAUCUUCCCUUGAAGCGUGUACCUGCCAACUUCAGGGCCUGUCACCUCAGAACUCCAAGGACUUCGUACAAAUGGUCCGAAAGAUCCCAUAUCUGGGAUUUUGUUCCUGUGAAGAAUUAGGAGAAACUGGAAUAUGGCAGCUGACAGAUCCACCAAUCCUUCCUCUUACCCAUGGACCAACUGGGGGCUUCAACUGGAGAGAGACCUUGCUUCAAGAAUAAACCACACCAGUGAACAAGAAGGAAAGGCCUUUUGGAGUGUGUCUUUCUGUGUGUUUAAAAACAGUGGGAAAAUCCACACCACACUCUAAGUGGACAGCUCAGAAUAAUUUAGCAUAUUUCCUUUCACACUUAAAGUUCUUAAGAUGAGACUGUGUAAAUGAGAGAAAGACUUGAUUCAGAGGAAAAAAAUGUGUUCUCUCUGGACUCUUGCCUAGCUCACAAGGCUUUGGAGAAUUGUCUUCCUAAAUCGGGGCACCUGCUACAGAAGAGAAUGUUUCGUUCCCUCUGGGUAUGCACAGCUAAGGGGCCUCAUUUCUCCCAGAGGGAGCUGCUGGCCCGCUCUAAGGGGUGCAAGAGGAAGGAGUGUGCCCAGACCAGCUGGGGGAGCAUUGAAAGGACAGCUUGGGGAUGGAAUUUUUUUUUUUUUAUCUCCAUUUUCCAGUUAGGUAGAGCCAAGCUGAGGAAUCCUUUUAAGAUUAUUAGAAAACAUGCCCUGAAGAGAGUUGUUCUUAGGUUACACAUGAAAUCCUACCGUCACUAGCCCCCAUACACCAGUGUUGCUGGCUGAAGAUACCCGCUUAAGGAUGCUAACAUUUACCCUGGUACUGCCACAUUUUCUCUAGAGCAGCUGGCCCUUCUUGCUACAGCCCUAUCCCCCCUCCUUGCUUCUGUGAAAUGGGGAGACAAAGCACUUUUGCUCUCCAAAGCACUUUUGGAUACUCAGGAGGAAAGAUAAGAUACAUGUUUGAAGUAUUCAAUCAUAGGAGCAAAGAACUUGCAAAAUAUGAAGUGACUUGGAAUUAACCAUGUUGUAGCCUAACGUGCUACUGCAUUUCUAAAUCAUCAAUAUUUGCUUGUCUUUGCCCCUAGACUCUAGACUAUGUUAACUAGUUAAGGAUGUUACAUUUUGAAAGGAUGUAUGUUAGAUAUAUUAUUUGCAGCAAGAAGUUCAUUCUGUGCAAUAUGGACAUGUUUGCAAACCAUACCAAGGGUCAGGUUGUUGUACACUUACAGUACGUGUCAACCAUAAUGGAACAUCCACAAAUGCAUCAAUUAUACCAGGGAUGUAUAGUAAGUCAGGGAACUAAUAUAAAUGAUGACAGUCAUGGCUGCACUGCUACUUGUGCUGUCGUUUUGUUUGUUUUUCUAUGAUAAUUUAAAAUACAUAGGUAGGGCUACUGAGGAAAUUUGGAGAGCCACAUUCUGUGGUUUCUCAUUAUACUUACUUCCUGCAUUUAGAGGGAGUUUAUUUAAAAGAAAUAAAUGACAAUCAAACCAAAUCAUCAGUUAUCAAUGUCUGUUUAAUUGUGUGACUAUCUGACUGUUGAUGGCCACAGAUGAUGGUCUCCUAUGGUAUAGUUCACUCUGUAGAAGAUGUAUGCAAAGUGAAAUGCCAGCCCUUUAAAGAGACAUUAGUUAGUGUAAAAUGGAUCUUUACAUGUUGCAGUAACAUUGACUAUGUUUCAAAACUCAGAUGCAUAAAACGUAAGGUAUAUAAAAAUACAUCUAUGCUUGCGUUUGAAACUACAACUUGAUAACCCCUAGAAAGAAGAGGACAUGAAAGGAUGCUGGCUAUAUAUGUUAAUGAGCAAAAGGAUUAUAGUUGUUUUGUUUUGUUUUUAGAGACAGGGUCUCACUAUAAUGCUUAGACUGGUCUUGAACUCCUGGGCUCAAGCGAUCCUCCUGCCCCUGUCUCCCAAAGUGCUAGGAUUACAGGUGUGAGCCACCACACCUGGCCCAUAGUUGUAUUUUUUUUAGGUCACUUAGAAAAAUAUGUCAUGUAUUUUACAUUUUGAGAAACAAAUCAAUCAUGGUUUCUUCUAGCGUUGCGCAAACACUGACCCAGCUUCUGGGUAUGGAAAUAACCCUGUGAUGAUGUGUUAAUAUAAAAUGUUGGGAGGGAAUAUUCCCAAUAAAGGUCUUAAGAGAAAAGUCACAUUACAAGUAAUGUAAUGGCUCUACCAUUCAUUCUUCUGGUAUUUGUAAUGAAGUGAAUCCACUGUUUAAUCAGAUCCAUAAUCUUUAACAGAUUCACCACAAAUUUUCAUGGGCGUUGAGUGCUCAGAAUAAUGCUUGAACACCUCACCUUGAAACUGUAGCAGUGUGUUCUGGGCAGUAUCUGUAAUGUAUGAAAUAGAGUCUGGAAUAGGUUAUCCACUCCAUCUUCUAGGUUAUCUUAGUUGUAUGACGAACUGAUAAAUCUGUCUGACUGGGCUACAAUCCAUUGUUCUUAGUCCAAUAUGGACACUGCCUUAGGCAAUGGUCUAUAUAAGCAAAAGGAGAUAGAGAUCUGAAAUAAUUUUCCGAAUAAUUCAGGUGGAAAACAAGAAAGAUUGUAUUUCUCUGCUUUCAUUUCAAUUUCAUUAUUUCAAAUUGCUUGUCAAAAUGGCCCAAAAGAUCUGAAUUCACAUUAAGUUCCCCUUGCACACUUACCUAUUUAAAAAACUAAACUUGCACUGCAACUGAGAAAUUAUUUGUAAAUCAUGUGGCAUCUAUGUAUAAUAAAAGAAAGAGACAACUAUAUUACUCAAUUUCAUAUACAUCCAAAAAGUAUAGGCUAAUAUAUAUAACCUGAAGUUGCAGCUGGUUCUUUUUGAUCUGAAGCUGAUGCUUAUUAAAACAAAUGAUGUAUGGGGAGAGGAGAAGGAAGGGCAAGGAAGGAAUUGACAGAUAAGAAGCAAAUGGUUUCUUGUACAGAGGAAUUUUGUUUUAAUGUAGAAAGUUAUUUGAAAUAAACUAGGUGAAAUGAAAUUAACUAAAGGUUUUAAUCUGGGAUUGAAAGCCUGAAAGCAUUUCCUGCUUCUACAAGUGUGCCACAUCAAUCCGGUAAUGCCCCAGUGUUAUUCACAGACAGAACUUUGUUUCCUGUGAUUUUAAAAUACCGCGUCUGUUCCUCCAUGGACCAGAGUAAUUGGCACAUUUUAAUGCAUAAGCUGGGGGUUUCAUUUUCCCAGGCUCUCUUCACCAUCACUGCAUUGGUAGCUAGGAGCUUAUUGCUUCACCCCAGUAUGGAGUUCAGAUUACAGUGUUUUCCAUUACAUUUAGAUUCAUAGAAUCUGAAUGGCUGAUUAAAUGGCCAUCUGAUGGCUGAAAGAGGGGCGUAUUUUUCACUCUGUAGUGAAAGGCUUGGAGGAGUUUCUACUUUUUAUUUUAAUUAUACUUUAACCAAAGAAUUAUUUUAAAGUAACCUUAUAUUUAAAAGAUGAUUUUGCAAAAAAUAAAAAAUAAAAAAUAUGCCUUCUGGAGUGAUGUCUGUUUGGUAAAUCAUUGUUGAUAAUUUCCUUGUUAGUGGUAUUUGGAAUGCAUAUAGAUUGUCUUGUCAUUGUGCUUAACAUUACCAUAAGUGUGUCUUUUCCACUCAACUAGCUGUAUUCGUAUUAAAAUGAAGUCUCUUAUUUCAAUUACCUAGUGUUGUUGGGAACUAAUUGAACAGCUACAGUAAAAGAAGUUCCUAUCUCAUUGCCUUUGUGGAAAGGCUUCCCUAUGUGGUAAAAGAAAGGCAUUCCUCCGUAACCUAGGCACUCUGCAAGUCCAGUGUUUAAUUUCAAAGCAGUGAUGAAUUGCUCUUUUGAAAUUACUCUAAGUAAUCCAUGUGUUAGAAUACAGAUGAACCUCCGUUUGAUUUCACAGCCUUCAGCACAGGCAACUGUUACUGAGUCUGCACGAACUUAGAUAAUGAGGUGCAGGGUUAUUUGCAUUUAAAUUGCAAUCCAGCACACGUGUGAGAAAGAAGAGGCACUAGUCUAAAAGGCUGCAUUGCGGGGAGAGAUGAGACAGGCAGAGGAGGGUGGGGUAAAGAGCGAUUUAACAUCUAUUUAGGUUAAUGUUCACUUUACAAAGGUGAUGGGGGAUAUUUUGUUAGGUGAUAGCAGAAGCUUUUCAUUUUUAAACAUAGAAUUAAAAUUGGAUUUGCUUCUCUUUAAUACUUCAACAUAUUGAAUUUCCCUAGGAAAGUGACUAGCUAUAAUGAAAAUUCAAGCGAAAAGGGAAAAAGAUUGUAAAUGCAGAUGAAAUAACUUCAUUUUUAAGUACAAAUAAUAGUAGGAUUGGUGUAUGUAGGUUUAAAAUUAUAGUGAUGACUAGUCGAACUUAAUAUACAAUCAGUUCUUGCAAAUACUUUACACUUAGCUGCCAUUACACAACAAAUUGGAAUUUUCCAGCUGUUCAACUAUCAUGGACUCUGUACAGGAUAGAUGUGUAUAAUGGAAAAUAUGUACUGCUUCUUUCUUUGAUUGCCACUCAAGAUGGAAACACCAUGCCAAGGCAUUUUGGUUAUACACAGAUCAUUCUAAACCUGUUAUUUUGGAGAGGUGUAUUGGUUUCUUUCUCAUUUAUAAGGCUAUUGUAUUUUUUUUUGUAUGUGAUUCAGGUGUAUUUAUUUGAAGACUAUUUGUAGUUAUAGGAAAACCACACCUACCUGUAUUGCCAAAUUCUUUGUAAACUCUCCGUGGCACUUGUGCUUUCCUGGCUGAGAGCUCUCCCCUGUUGAUACAGCUAUGGCACCAUUGUAAUUACAGAUGCACCUUUCAGGAGCAUCUCCAUUAAAUGGUUCAUAGAUGAUUUAAUAAAAAGAAACUUCUCAGUUGA